UGGAGAUUUGAUGGGAAUAAACCAGAUGCCUUAGGUCUCAAUACUCGGCUGUACAGGUGGAUACCCCAGAAUGACCUUCUAGGUCAUCCAAAAACCAGAGCUUUUAUAACUCAUGGUGGAGCCAAUGGCAUCUACGAGACAAUCUACCAUGGGAUCCCUAUGGUGGGCAUUCCAUUGUUUUUUGAUCAAUCUGAUAACAUUGCUCACAUGAAGGCCAAGGGAACAGCUGUUAGAGUGGACUUCAACACAAUGUCGAGUACAGACCUGCUGAAUGCACUGAAGACAGUAAUUAAUGAUCCUUCAUAUAAAGAGAAUAUUAUGAAAUCAUCAAGAAUUCAUCAUGAUCAACCAGUGAAGCCCUUGGAUCGAGCAGUCUUCUGGAUUGAAUUUGUCAUGCGCCACAAAGGAGCCAAACACCUUCGAGUUGCAGCCCAUGACCUCACCUGGUUCCAGUACCACUCUUUGGAUGUGAUUGGGUUCCUGCUGGCCUGUGUGGCAACUGUGCUAUUUAUCAUCACAAAGUGUUGUCUGUUUUGUUUCUGGAAGUUCGCUAGAAAAGGAAAGAAAGGAAAAAGGGAUUAGUUAAAUCUGAGAUUUGAAGCUGGAAAACCUGAUAGAUAGGGAUACUUCAGUUGAUUCCAGCAAUAAAUAUUGUGAUGCAAGAUUUCUUUCUUCCUGUGACAAAAAAAAAAAAAUCUUUUCGAAAUCUACCUUGUCAAGUAAAAAUUUGUUUUUCAGAGAUUUACCACCCAGUUAAUGGUUAGAAAUAUUUUGUGGCAAUGAAGAAAACACUAGGGAAAAUAAAAAAUAACAUAAAGCCGUACAAGCUCAUAUUGAAAUUUGUUGCACUUAUAUUGAAAUUUGUUGUUCUAAUUCACAAGUUACAUGAAAAAAAUUUACUCAGCUUAACUAUAUUUCACACAUUUUACAUAAACACAAGAACAUUAAGAAGUCUACUGACAGUAUCAGUACUGUUUUGAACAUACUCAGAAUAAUUUAGCUUCAUUUUGAACAGGAUUCUGUUGUUUUAACUGUUGCUGAAGAAACUAUUACAUAGUUAAAUUGUUUAGAAAGUCUCUCUCUUCGUUUUGAUAUUUUGAGAUGAGUAGUAUUGCUUGGCUUUUAUGAUGCAUGCAGCUUUAUUGUCACAUUUUUUGCUAAAAUUUAUGGCCAAAUGUUUACUGUUUUAAGCACAUAAGUCAUUUCUCAGUGGAAAUUAUGUGGAAUUAGAAAUAUAGCCACUCUUUCCUGCUUCCUACUGUAAAUUUGAACUAUUCUGCAACAUCUUUGGUUUCACAAGCCAAUUCUAUUUUUUCCAGAUAUUUAAAAAUAUUCAUCUGUUUGAUUUUAUUCUCAUAUUUUUAAUUAUUUCAAUAGCUAUUUGGGAACAGGUGGUGUUUGAUUAGAUGGAUAAGUUCUUUAGUGGUAAUUUCUGAGGUUUUAGUGCACACAUCACAUGAGAAGUGUACCCUGCACUCAAUGUGUAGUCUUGUAUCCCUCACCCCCUCCCACCCUCUCCUCUGAAUCCUUAGAACCCACUAUAUCAUUCUUAUGCCUUUGCAUCCCCAUAGCUUAGAUCCCAUUUAUAAGUGACAAUUUAGAAUGUUCAGUUUUCUAUUCCUGAAUUACUUCACUAAGAAUAAUGCCCUCCCACUUUGUACAAGUUGCUGUUAAUGCCAUUAGUUUGUUUAUUUUUAUGGCUUAGUAGUAUUCCAUGGUGUAUAUAUAUAUAGUAUGUAUAUGUGUGUGUAUAUGUGUGUGUGUGUGUGCGCGCACGCGUGUGUGUGUGUAUACAUUUUCUUUAUCCACCUAUUGGUUGGUUGAUGGGCAUUUAGGCUACUUCCAUUCUUUUUUUUUUAAUUGCAAACAGUGCUGUUGGAAACAUAUAUGUGUGUGGGUCUUUUUCAUAUAAAGACUUCCUUUCCUCUGUAAAGAUACACAGUAGUGGGAUUGCUGGAUUAAAUGGUACUUCUACUGUUAUUUCUUACAGGAAUCUUCAUAUGGUUUUCCAUAGUAGUUGUACUAGUUUACAUUCCCAUAGCAGCAUAAAACUGUCCCCUUUUUACCACAUCUAUGCCAACAUUUUAUUAUUUUUGGAUUUUUAAAUUAUAUUCAUUCUUUCAGGAGUAUAGUGGUAUUGCAUUGUGGUUUUGAUUUGCAUUUUCCUGAUAAUUAGUGAAGUUGAGCAUUUUUUCAUAUAUGUUGGCCAUUUAUAUAUCUUCUUUUAAGAAUUGUCUAUUUAUUACCUUAGGCUACUUUUUGAUGGGUUUUUUUCUUUUUUUUUUUUUUUUAGCCAUUUGUGGAUUCUGGACAUUAGCCUUUUGGUGUGAGAUGCAUAGUUCAUGAAUAUUUUCCACUACUCUGUGAGUUGUCUGUUUACACAGCUGAUUAUUUCUUUUGCUGGCAGAAGCUUUUUAGUUUAAUUAAAUCACAACUAUUUAUCUUUGUUUUAGUUGCAUUUGCUUUUGGAUUUUUGGUCAUGAGGUUUUUGCCUAACCCAAUGUCUAGAAGAGUUUUUCCAGUGUUACCUUCUAGAAUUUUUUAUUGUUUCUGAUCUUAGUUUUCACUAUUUGAUCCAUCUUGAGUUGAUUUUUUAUAAGGUGGGAGACAAAGGUGAAGUUUCAUUCAUCUACAUGUGGAUUGCCAAUUAUUCCAGCCCCAUUUGUUGAAUAGAGUGUCAUUUCCCCUUUAUGUUUUUGUUUGCUUUGUCAAAGUUCAGUUGGCUAUAAGUAUUUGUCUUUAUUUCUGGAAUCUCUAUUCUGUACAUGCCUGUUUUCAUACUGAUACCAUGUUGUUUUGGUAACUUUUAAUGUGCCUUAUAAUACAUUGGGUAAUGUAAUGCCUCUAGGUUUGUUCUUUUUUGUAGUCUUUCUUUGACUAUGCAGGUUUCAAAGCCGAGAAUCAAAUAAAGAACUCAUCCAUUUUGAAAAUAGCUGCAAAAAAAAAAAAAAAGAAAGAAAGGAAAACAAAACAAAUUACUGAGGAAUAUAUGAGGAAUAUACCUAACAAAGAAGGUUAAAGACCUCUACAAAGAAAACUACAAAACACUGCUGAAAAACGUCAUAGAUGACACGAACAAAUGGAAAUACAUCCCAUGCUCAUGGAUGGGUAGAAUCAAUUUUGUGAAAAUGAGCAUAUUGCCAAAAUAAAUCUAUAAAUGCAAUUCAAUUCUCAUCAAAAUACAAUCAUCAUGCUUAAGAGAACUAGAAAAAAAAAUCCUAAAUUUCAUAUGGGUUUUAUUAUCAUUUUUGGCCUUUAAUAAAAAAUGUAAGUCCUUAAUUUUAGGUUGUGAUCAUAUAGAAAUUGCACUCUAAAGGGACUUAGUGAAUUUUCAAUCUUGUUAAACAUACAUGUACAUAUACAUGUCCAUUUCUUUUAAAACAAGACACAGCAUCAAUUAACUAGCUAAUAGGUAUGUUAUUGAAUUUAAAAUUCAAAGUGUGUUUUGAAGACAGCUUGAAAUAAUUAUUAUUAUUCUACAUAACUAUAUUUUAAAUGAUCAUAUCUAUUUUUUUAUUUUCCACAGAGAUUUUUGAUUCAUCCCUCCUACAAAUGUAAUAUGGAAACAUAAAUUUUUUAGUAAGUCAAAAAUAUUUACAAAGAAUACAAGAAGUUUAUAAAUUUUGUGGAAAAUACUUAAAUUAAGCCAUCAAUCUCCUUUAAUCUACAUAUCAGCGAAGCAUUUUAUGAUCAAACUAGUCCAGAUUGACAGAAACCUAGUUGUCUUUGUCACUAAAAAGUCUUACCAUUUACCAAUUUUCACAAAAAAUAUUCUCCGGCACAAGGUGUGAUUAAAAACAAAUAUAUUUAUAUAUAUAUAUAUAUUUAUAAUUACAUAGACAUAGAUAAAUCACGUUUAUAUAUAUAUAUAUAUAUAUAUAUAUAUAUAUACACACACACACACACACUCUAAAACAUUGAUAAGAUGGAGGAAUUAUAGAAAAUUUUAUGCAAAUCUUCUAGGAAUUAAUAAAGAUAUAAAGAAAAGCAGAACUUAUAUAGUGCCAAAGAUUAAUAAUGUUGUUUUAUCAUGCUUAUAAACCUGUAUUAAUUCACAUAAAACCUAUCCUAUAACACGCAUAACAAAAGAUUGGUAUCCAUUGUUCAGUGAGUACUAGAAAUCACUAACCAAAACCGACAAACAAUCUAAUAAAAAAUUGAUUAAAAUAUGAAGAAGCAAUUCGAAGUAAAAAUGGCCCAUAAGAUAUAAAAGAUUAAAAAGUUACUGAUGCUUAGUAAAAUAGAAAUAAUGCCAACAAAUUGAUGUCAUAGAGAAGAUUUUCACCCUAUAAAAACCUGAGAAAUCUAUUUUUGAGGAAGUAAAUUUGAAAUAACACUUUUAAAUAAAAUGUGAAUAUGCCGUUUGAAACUGAAGUUCUACAUCUAGGAAUCUGUCAUGCAGAAAUCCGUGCAUAUAAGCACAUGUAUGAACAGAAUGAUUUCUCCAGCACUUAAAUGGCUUUCAGUCAAUGAACACAUGUACCUCCAACAAAUGUAUGAGGGUAGCCAUUGCAGAGAACAGGUUCAUUAUCACAUUGCUAAACAGAAAAAGUAGUUUCCAGAAAAACAAAAAAACGUAUUUUUUCAAUGAAAUAAAGUAUAUGUAAACUGUUACAAAGAAGAAAGAAUCUUGAAAAAUACAUGUAAUUACAAGGAUGAGAAUUUAAAUUUUUAUUCUAUAUAAUUCUGCAAUGUUUAACUUUUCACAAACGUUUUCAUGUAUUAAUUAUGAGAUUUAAAGUUUAAUUUGUGAAAUGAACACAGCAAUUCAAGACAGGAAGUUCCAAAAUGUAACAUCACAAAUUAAUUUAUUAGUGUCAUUCAAAAAACUUGAUAAUGUUUCUUGUAUGUUAUCUAUUUUAUCCACUUGCAGCUUGUUUUUAGAACAUUUGUUCUGUUUUUGAAAAUAUGUUUGAAUAAAUAAAAUACAAUGUUUAAAAAUU